GUGCCUUUAGCUCCAGCCACCUCUUUAAGAGGAAACUGUUGGGCAGAUGGAGGAGGGCUAGUCACGGAAAGAAACUGUAAGCUGGACUGGGUGUGAGGAGGGGAGGUAAUAAAAGGAUUAUAGGGUGGAGGAGCAGAGGCUGAGGAAGAAUUGGGACCUAGCUCGGCCUGAUCUUCAGUUGCUUCAGGCCAUUUGAACGUAUAUGAGCCGGUCGUAGGGGAUAUGAUGGCUUAGCUUGGGCUCAGAGGCCUGAAAAUCGCCCCCACCAAUCACCUGUUUCCCCCAAUCUACCCUCCUGAAGGUCACUGACAAAGACUUCAUUGUCUCCUAGGAGAGGCUGCCAUAUAUCCAGGGCUGACGUAAUUCCAUCUUAAUAUCAGUUACAUUAUAAAAAUUUACCUCGUGCCUGAGGCCCCAGAGCCCAAGGGUGCAAAGCAGUAAUUGGUCAAAGUUCAACUUCCCUCCCACUCUGGGCUCAGGCUGUCCCCUGAGGGCCUGUGUUUUGAGUCUCUUUCCAGAACCUUGGUGUGAACUUAGGUCUUGGCGUCGGGAUCCCUUUUCGUCACACUCAGGUGACCUACAGGGAGCUCCGCUCGACACUGCAAGGCUUAGACCAGUUCGGUCCAACAGAGAAAGCAGGCAACCACCAUGUCAUUUGAAAACAGUUUCAUCGGGAUAUAAUUCGCAACCCAUACAGUGAAUCCAUUUAAGAUACUCUGACCCAUGGAUCCCCUGGGUGCAGCCAAGCCACAAUGGCCAUGGCGCCGCUGUCUGGCCGCACUGCUAUUUCAGCUGCUGGUGGCUGUGUGUUUCUUCUCCUACCUGCGUGUGUCCCGAGACGAUGCCACUGGAUCCCCUAGGGCUCCCAGUGGGUCCUCCCGACAGGACACCACUCCCACCCGCCCCACCCUCCUGAUCCUGCUACGGACAUGGCCUUUCCACAUCCCUGUGGCUCUGUCCCGCUGUUCAGAGAUGGUGCCCGGCACAGCCGACUGCCACAUCACUGCCGACCGCAAGGUGUACCCACAGGCAGACAUGGUCAUCGUGCACCACUGGGAUAUCAUGUCCAACCCUAAGUCACGCCUCCCACCUUCCCCGAGGCCGCAGGGGCAGCGCUGGAUCUGGUUCAACUUGGAGCCACCCCCUAACUGCCAGCACCUGGAAGCCCUGGACAGAUACUUCAAUCUCACCAUGUCCUACCGCAGCGACUCCGACAUCUUCACGCCCUACGGCUGGCUGGAGCCGUGGUCCGGCCAGCCUGCCCACCCACCGCUCAACCUCUCGGCCAAGACCGAGCUGGUGGCCUGGGCGGUGUCCAACUGGAAGCCGGACUCAGCCAGGGUGCGCUACUACCAGAGCCUGCAGGCUCAUCUCAAGGUGGACGUGUACGGACGCUCCCACAAGCCCCUGCCCAAGGGGACCAUGAUGGAGACGCUGUCCCGGUACAAGUUCUACCUGGCCUUCGAGAACUCCUUGCACCCCGACUACAUCACCGAGAAGCUGUGGAGGAACGCCCUGGAGGCCUGGGCCGUGCCCGUGGUGCUGGGCCCCAGCAGAAGCAACUACGAGAGGUUCCUGCCACCCGACGCCUUCAUCCACGUGGACGACUUCCAGAGCCCCAAGGACCUGGCCCGGUACCUGCAGGAGCUGGACAAGGACCACGCCCGCUACCUGAGCUACUUUCGCUGGCGGGAGACGCUGCGGCCUCGCUCCUUCAGCUGGGCACUGGAUUUCUGCAAGGCCUGCUGGAAACUGCAGCAGGAAUCCAGGUACCAGACGGUGCGCAGCAUAGCGGCUUGGUUCACCUGAGAGGCCGGCAUGGUGCCUGGGCUGCCGGGAACCUCAUCUGCCUGGGGCCUCACCUGCUGGAGUCCUUUGUGGCCAACCCUCUCUCUUACCUGGGACCUCACACGCUGGGCUUCACGGCUGCCAGGAGCCUCUCCCCUCCAGAAGACUUGCCUGCUAGGGACCUCGCCUGCUGGGGACCUCGCCUGUUGGGGACCUCACCUGCUGGGGACCUCACCUGCUGGGGACCUUGGCUGCUGGAGGCUGCACCUACUGAGGAUGUCGGCGGUCGGGGACUUUACCUGCUGGGACCUGCUCCCAGAGACCUUGCCACACUGAAUCUCACCUGCUGGGGACCUCACCCUGGAGGGCCCUGGGCCCUGGGGAACUGGCUUACUUGGGGCCCCACCCGGGAGUGAUGGUUCUGGCUGAUUUGUUUGUGAUGUUGUUAGCCGCCUGUGAGGGGUGCAGAGAGAUCAUCACGGCACGGUUUCCAGAUGUAAUACUGCAAGGAAAAAUGAUGACGUGUCUCCUCACUCUAGAGGGGUUGGUCCCAUGGGUUAAGAGCUCACCCCAGGUUCUCACCUCAGGGGUUAAGAGCUCAGAGUUCAGACAGGUCCAAGUUCAAGCCCAGGACCACCACUUAUAGGGUACAGGUGGGAUCGACUGUAAAUGAGGACUUCUGGAACAUUCCAAAUAUUCUGGGGUUGAGGGAAAUUGCUGCUGUCUACAAAAUGCCAAGGGUGGACAGGCGCUGUGGCUCACGCCUGUAAUCCCAGCACUUUGGGAGGCUGAGGUAGGAGGAUUGAUUGAGGCCAAGAGUUAAAGACCAGCCUGGUCAAUAUAGCAAGACCACGUCUCUAAAUAAAAAAUAAUAGGCCGGCCAGGCA